AUUUUGUCUGUAUGUGUUAGUUUCAAAAACCUAAGUCAGAGGAAUUCAUAUUUUGUAAUUUGGAAUAUCCUUAAAAAACAUCUUAUACUCAUUUUGAUUACUGCAGUGUAAAUAUCCUAAGCUUUUGAUUGGUGUACUGGAAUUUUGGUCUGUAGUUGAAUUUCUAGAAAGAAGAAAACAUAGGAGAGAAUAAAUUAGUAGCAGAAUAUUAGGUAUGAUUUAUUUAAGUAGAGUCCAGGAUCCGCUUUGAGGUCACUAUAUUUGUGUGUUCCAAAUUCUAAGUGGUCAUUGAGUCCCAUAAGCAGAGUACAGUAAUGUUUUAAAAUAAUGUUUAACAGAAAUGAUUUGGUGCUACAUUGUAUUAAAGUGUAAAAUUGACCCCAGAGCUAGAUUUUAAAAUCUUUGUAGUUAAUUAGGCUUCAUGUUGGACCUGCCCAAAAAAAGAAUGAAGGACUGAGAUAUUUCAAGAUGGUACUUGUCCAAACCAAAUGAGCUGAGAGAUUUUGGUGUGCUUCACUUGGUUCCCUGACUUGAUAGGUCAGCCCGGACAGUUAUCUUCCCAUGGUGACUUCCCCCAGCCACCCAAGCACUAGGCUGCCUGUUCUAGUAAUUUAUCAGUUGUUUUGGAAAUGACUGUGUUCUCUUGCAUUUGUGUCAUUUUAUUGAUAGUUUGGAUAAUAAGUAUCUUGAGGAAAAGCAAAAGCCAUAUCAUGUAAUGGCAAAAUUAAUGAGCACACGUAAGUUUUUUUAAGAGCUAUUGUUAUGUCACUGUACCCGUGAAUAUACUUUUUUAACUUAGCCACCUGUCUCCAGCUUUGUAACUGUCAGAGAUCAUGAACCCUGUGAGAAAUAGAGGAGGAGGAAGGGACUAAUGUGUUAUAUGUAUGCAGGCUUGUAUGCUGGUCAUUUUACCUACUUUUUCACUUAUUUCUCAACAGUCCUGUGAGGAAACAAAUAGGCCCAGUUUCUGAUAAAUGCAUCCAUGGUUACCAGGUGGGGACCAAGGCAUACUGAACACAUUUUUUAGCAGCUGGGCAACAACAGAUAUCAGAAAACACCUGCCGUUUAUUUAUAACCUAAGCAGCAUCUCUAUAUACUCCUACCUCCCGGCAUUUAAAGUGUUUGGUGCAAGUGCCAAAGUUGUGCAUUUCCUGGGACGAGUCAAACCAUGGAAUUAUACUUAUGAUCCCAAAACAAAAAGUGUCAAAAGUGAGGCCCAUGAUCCCAACAUGACUCAUCCAGAGUUUCUCAUCCUGUGGUGGAACAUCUUUACCACCAACGUUUUACCUCUGCUUCAACAAUUUGGCCUUGUCAAAGACACCUGCUCAUAUGUAAAUGUGGAAGAUGUCUCAGGAGCCAUAUCACAUCUGUCCCUUGGGGAGAUCCCAGCUAUGGCACAGCCGUUUGUAUCCUCGGAAGAACGGAAGGAACGAUGGGAACAGGGCCAGGCUGAUUAUAUGGGAGCAGAUUCCUUUGACAACAUCAAGAGGAAACUUGACACUUACCUCCAGUAGAAACACUGCAUUUUUCUGUGAACACAUCCACUUCACAAGCCUUGUUUCUGAUACUUAGUAUCUAGAGCUGGGUUGAGAAAAGUCUGUUACAGUUGCUAGAGGUUUUCAUUAAAACUUAUCAGAUGAGAGGCUUUUUUAGGAUAAGAGGUGAGAACUGGGCAAAAGUUGUGAAGCAGCAAUUCUGUUAUAUGGACAGUGUUCUGCUUUUUAAUCCUAUUUAGCUUGUUUCAGAAAUUCUCACUUUUGUUGACUGCCAACAUACAAAGUAAGGGAAACUCAAGAUAUUAAGAUGGCUGUAUCAGUUCUUAAAAUCUGCAGAGCCUGGUUCAAAAUCAGUCACUCCCUUCAGAAGCAGACAUGGCAUCUGUUCCUUGCUUGCUUGUUGGUUGUGUACCUUUCACGAGACCUGAAUUUUAGAAUUGCCCAGUGCUGCCAGAGUGAGUGAGUGUAAUUCUCCUUUCAGGUAAAGAUAGGCUAUCUCAACACUGCUGAGUGAUUCAUAAACAUAUCAACCAAUAGCAUUAACCCAUUUUAUUUCCUGUCCUUAGUGUCUGAAGAUGCUCACCAGUUUUCUGUGUACAGUAAGGCAGCAUGCUAAAAUGCUUUUGUUCAGUUCUGUAUAUUUGAAAAUAGCAGUGUGUUCUCUGAUGGUUACCUGCAGUGGCACCCUGUACAAAAAAUAAAAGACUUAUUGCUGUAUCUUGGUUGUUUAAUUAAAUUAAGGAAUUUCACCAUACACCCUUGAACAAAUCUAUUAGGGAAUUUUUCACAAUUUUUGGAAUUUGUCAUAGUUUUAAAAAAGUGUAAAGCUUGACAUUGGGAUAUAUGCUUUAAAAACUGGUAUCUAUGAUUUCAAUCUAAUUGUUUUUCUGUGAUGGUGAUGGAUCUGACAGAUCAGAACAAACCGAGAUCAAACUUACAUAGUGUCAUCCACACUGCACCUCUCUAUUAAGUGGGUAUUUAGCUAUUUAGAAUAUUUUAACCUUAAAGUCAUUCCUAACUGUCAGAAUCAAUACUGGGUCCAGUCCCUACUAGUAUUUUAUCUAUGAUUUAAAAUGAUAGAAUGGAAAAGCGUAUUUAUUAAAUUUAUAGAUCAUUCUAGGUUGUAAGAGAUGGCAAGCUAAAGAAGGGUAGGAUCCAAGAUGACCUUUUAAAACUAAAAUGAGUGGUCAGAAAUGAUUCUAUGGAAGAAAACAGGACAGUUAACCAUGACAGGAAGAAACUUUAGAGGUUUGAUUGGGCAAAAGCUGCAAAGCUUUUGUGACUUAGCCUUCAAAGUCACCCUCCUUAUUCAUAUUGAUGUGAAUUAAUAUACAAGCAUAUAGACAGCUUAAGUCAAGAAUGGUUGGGGCCACCUUGAAGGCUGUUACCAUAGGAGCUCAAUAAGAACCUGAGGAUUUACCUAGAAUUAUAAAAUAUUAAAUGAUAAAUGACUUCUGAAACUAGCUAUUUGGACUGGUGAAGAAUGAGUCGCUAUUGAUCUUCAAGUACAAUGAAGCAUUUACCAAAGAUUUAUUUAAGUGCCUCCAUGUGUCAGAUGCUGUGGUACAAAGAAGGACUUCUCAAAAUUUUAGCUAGUCAGAGGUCUUUCUGGCUUCCGAGUCCCUGGUUAAGAUGAACAGAAACACAGUCUUCAGAUAUAAAAUGUCUUAUUUUUGUGGCCAUUCAGUUGCAUUCAACGUUAAUUUUUUCUAUUUACUACCGUUCAUUCUCUAUUUUUUACACAGUAGCAUAACAAAGCUCUAAGGUGGAAAAGCUGACAUAGUUUUAAAUUUUUUUUUUUUUUUUUUUUUUUCUUGAGGCAGAGUCUUGCUCUGUCAGUCAGUCACCAGGCUGGAGUGCAGUGGUGCAGUCUCGGCUCACUGCAACCUCUGCCUCCUGGAUUCAAGAGAUUCUCCUACCUCAGCCUCCUGAGUAGCUGGGACUACAGGCACGCACCACCACGCCCAGCUAAAUUUUGUAUUUUUAGUAGAGACAGGUUUCACCAUGUUGCCAGGAUGGUCUCAAUCUCUUGACCUCGUGAUCCACCGGCCUUGGCCUCCCAAAGUGCUGGGAUUACAGGCGUGAGCCACUGCACCCAGCAAAUUUUUAAAUUUCAAAUAAGUAGUGAAGGCUAUUAUUAACUUUUGGAAUCAGAAAGAAUGACAAGCUUACCAUAAGACAUAGCAUAUAAUGCUGUCAAGUUAUUUGGCUAGAAAAUCACUGAACUAAACAUUCUUUUCCUUCUAUGAUCUAUGUCUUAAGGUGAAGUAUUAACUAACUUUUCCAUGUAAAGCUAUACAAAUAUUGGAAAAUCUUUUCUAGGGAGUCCAGAAUACUAAGGGUUACUUAGUAAAAUGUAUAAAAAGGCAACAGUAAUUCAAAUUACAAGAUUUAUAUUUGCAGAGGUGAUCCAUAUAUACUUAUCCCCUUGCAGUGGCUGGUAUGACCUUUGGUUGUAAGACAAACUUGCCCACAACAGAGGUCAAAUCCAUGCCUUUGGAGAUUAGCUCCAUGGUGGAUGGAGCUAUGGUUUAUGCAUAAAGUAAAUGUUUGUUUACCUUAAUUCUCCUUAUACCCAUAUUGUCCUGCUGUAUAACACAUUUUGCAGAUAUUUUGAAGUUAAUGUGUUAAAAACUUGAGGUUAAACAUUUGAGUUUUUGUUAAGAGCCAAACAUCAAAUGUGCCCUUAUAUUUUUAAUGAAUCUCAUCCAAAUGCUAAUGCAUAAACCUUGACAAGUAGUAUAAAUAAAACAAGAAAAAAAUACAGCAAUGUCUUUGCCAUUCCCCAAAACAAAGCACACACUGCCGAAGAUCAUUAGUACUCACUGGUAACAAACUACAUAGGGUUAGUUUGUAUUUCCAAUUCUAGAGCUGUAAUUUUAAGGACAAAAUGUACAAUGAUUGAUUAAGAGUGCUAUCUGUGUAUAUAUAGGUAUUAUCACAACUCCUUUUUUUCUUCCAGAUGAAGAAAUUAAUUGGGACCAAUGUUUUUAGAUCAAGGCAUUUUAAAUAAGCACUCUUGAUUUCUGAACAAGAAUUUCAACCAGCUAAAUUGAGCAAAAUAAAGUUAGUUAGGAUAUGAGGACAUUAUUCUGUUACAGUAAUCUUCAUGUACUCUCAAAAAAAUGUAACACUUGCAUAGAAAUGUCACAAUUAAUGAAGGAUUUUAUUUGAAGAUAAAGUCAAAAUUAUGGCACCGAGGAAGGUAAUAAACAUUUGAAAUUUUUAUUGAUUUUUAAAUUUAAAAUCCAGUUUUAACCACAAAAUUGUUUGAAUCACAAGUGGUAAUACAAUGUCUUCAAUAUUUUUCUAAAGUUAUUUUUCUAUAUAAUAAUAAGACAACAGCAUAGCAUAUAGGAAGUUUUCAUUCCAGUGGCUUUUUUAUAUAUUUAUCCUUCUUAGGAAGGACAAAUUAAAUUUUUUAAAUUAAACUUUUAAAAUAUAACAACAUCUAACAGAACUGUACAAAACAAAGAGACAUUUUUUAAACAACUUGCCAAACUUACUUAUGAGUGUGUUUUAAAAACAACUUUGUAAAUGUCUGGGCAAAGAAGCAAGCUGUCCUCCCUUUACCUUCAUAGUGAGUUUGUAAGGCUUUGUCUUUGUAAGCAGAAAGAGUAGACUGUGUUGUUUUUUGCCAAAAACUGUUUAUACUUAAUCUCACUGAAGUAUUGCUAUAUGGAGAACCCAUACUCUGAUCAACUUGAUUUUUUGUGUGUAAUGCUUGAUCUACCAGGUAACUUCCCAACUGCUCCUAAUGCUAGCGGGCUAAUCCCACAUUAUUAUUCCACUAUCAUCCCUGCAGAAAGGUCUUGGUUUUGAUGAAAAUCAGCCCUUUCCUUACCUGCUACUGCCUCAAAAAGGGACCAGGAAGAUUCUAGCUGGCUAAUUCACUGUUCCCUUUGAGCAAGAAAACGGCACAGGGAGAAAAGGACUUAUCUGGUGAGAGAUUUGGCAUAUACCUUCAAUGUGUGCCCUAUAACACAACAUUGUCUCCGAUCUCAUCUUUCUAUCAAAUGACUUCCAACACUCUUAAGUCUCAGGUAUUCUUAAAUCUGUAUCAUCAAACAUGAAGCUUCUCUUGUUUGUUAGAGUAAUUAAUCUUUCUUUGGAUUAAAGUUUCCCUUUGAAAUAAAACCACCUACCUAAUCUGACUGCUAAAUUUCUAGCUUCUUUGUUUUAAAUAUGCUCAGGAGUCAACCCAAAUUCUGCAGCAAAUAAGUUUGCUUAUUAACAAAAAAGUAAAAAAAAAAGAAAAGAAAAAAGAUGACUAAUUCUACAGAUAGCUGUAAGGAUGAAUUACUCAAGUUCAAAAUCAAAUUCUGAUUCUAAACACAUAACAAUUGUUUACAUUCAGGAUUAAGAUGUCUUUAAGAGUUGAAACGACUUUGGAGAUCAUCCAGCCCAACUUCCAUCCAGAUAUCACGCCUCUCACAUAUAGUAGUCUUCUGAAUUAUAAAAAUUUAUAAAGUUACUUCCAAAAAAAGCUACAUAAAUAAAAAUUAUCUAUUUAUAGAAAUAUCUAUUUAGCAGUUCCAUAAUUUAAAAUAUUCAAAUCAAAUUGGGUAGGACUGGUUUGCCUCUCACUCCCACAGACUAUAUUUAUACCUCAGACACAGCAAGUUACAUUUAAACAAUGAGUGUAGUACUACUUAACUAAAAUGGAAAAAAUAGUACUCUUAACAUAAUCCCUAAUUUUUUCAUGAACAUAAAACUCCAAGUCAUUUAUGUGAACUAUAUCUCAAUGUAGCUGUAGGAAAAAUAAAAACCUGUGCUAACCUGGACUUUGGUCUCAUUUAAGAUUUGGUUCUGGAAUGCAAAUAUGGUUUUUGAAAGCCCAAUAAAAUUAAUUCUUGUAUA